GAGUCCACACUGCAAGUCCAGAGAGCAGGGAACUACCUUGAGUAUUCUACUCAAACUUAUGUCUCAGAGUUCCCCAAUUUCCCAAGAAGGGAGAGAUAGAGGCCACAAUCCAGGGGGCCAUCUCUUAAGGUACCAAUAAUUUUGCAGCCCAGUAGGAGUCAUGUACACGGUAUAAGACUUGGAGGAAAUGCAGGGACCCUUCUGUUUUCUCCUGCAAAGUUGAAAAAGCUGCAUGCAGUUGGAAGGGAUCUUCAGAUGGUGCUGGUGACUUUCUGUUCCUUUUGGAGUUGACAUGCAUGUGGAUUGGAGGAAAAAUAAUCAACAUAUAUUCUCCUUUCGUACUGUUUAAAUCACAGGAAGAAGCGGCUUUAAGACAAAGAUCAAACCAAAAUGACAACUGCUCACUUUUACUGUCAAUACUGCACAGCAUCACUUCUUGGGAAGAAAUAUGUACUAAAGGAUGACAGUCCAUACUGUGUUACAUGUUAUGAUCGUGUAUUUUCUAACUAUUGCGAGGAAUGCAAAAAACCAAUUGAAUCUGAUUCUAAGGAUCUUUGUUACAAAGACCGGCACUGGCAUGAAGGAUGCUUCAAGUGCACCAAAUGCAAUCACUCUUUGGUGGAAAAGCCUUUUGCUGCCAAGGAUGAGCGCCUGCUGUGCACGGAGUGCUAUUCUAACGAGUGCUCCUCCAAGUGCUUCCACUGCAAGAGGACCAUCAUGCCUGGUUCCCGCAAAAUGGAAUUUAAGGGAAACUACUGGCAUGAAACCUGUUUUGUGUGUGAGAAUUGCCGACAACCUAUAGGGACAAAGCCUUUGAUCUCCAAAGAGAGUGGCAAUUAUUGUGUGCCAUGUUUUGAGAAGGAGUUUGCUCACUACUGCAACUUUUGUAAGAAGGUGAUAACUUCAGGUGGGAUAACAUUUUGUGACCAGCUAUGGCAUAAAGAGUGUUUUCUGUGUAGUGGCUGUAGGAAAGAUCUCUGUGAAGAACAGUUCAUGUCCAGAGACGACUAUCCAUUCUGCGUGGACUGCUACAACCAUCUUUAUGCCAACAAGUGUGUAGCCUGUUCCAAACCCAUUAGUGGUCUCACAGGUGCCAAGUUUAUCUGCUUUCAAGACAGCCAGUGGCAUAGCGAAUGCUUUAACUGCGGGAAAUGCUCUGUCUCCUUGGUGGGUAAAGGCUUCCUGACCCAGAACAAGGAAAUCUUCUGCCAAAAAUGUGGCUCCGGAAUGGACACUGACAUCUAGGAGACAGUCCUUGCCCACCUAAAAUCCAUUUUGCCUUCGUUGUCACUAAAGCCAGAACUCAGUUGCGGUCUUAUUUUUGACUUAAGUUUUAGAAAAUAUUCAUGUAGUUUAGAGUGGAAAAGUUUUUGCACACAUUUUGAUCGAACUAUAUUCUAAGCACACAAAAAGCACAGUAGAACAGAAAUGAAUAUAUGCUAAAUCACAAAGACAACUCUCCUUGCAAAAUACUGCACUCUGCUGUUAGAAGCAGAGGAAAAUAUCUCUUCAUAAUCAAAUAUAUGACAUAUACCUAGGAGCUGUGGAUGUAAUUACUGAAGAAUGAGGUUUUUCAUACCUGAAGAGUAAAAGAAAAACUAAGAGAUCAAACUGAGAGGUAUACAUGAGGCUAGUGUUUGCAUUCCUGGUUAUAUGUAAUGUGAUAAAUUAGCUAUGAAUGGUAAAAGAACAAAACUGAUCAGAGUAAAUUCAUUAGCAAUUAUCACAUUUAAGAAUUGUUAUCAUUUAAAAAUCAUCCUUUUUUUCACACAUACUGACUGUAGAAUUAAAAAACAAAGCUACAAUUUGCCCUCAUACACACUGCUUCCACAGCUUGCUAGUUCUGUGUUUACUCAAUGGAAUAUGAGAACUGAGGACAUUAUGGCUCUCAUAAUCUGCAUAGGUAUAAAGAGGAUCAUUUCUACCUAGGGAUAGCCAAAGCAUGGGUUUCAACACGUUUUGUAUUAAAUAUAUUUUCAAAGUCCACAGUGAUUUUUCUAAACGCUUACAGAUUCCAUGAAAUAAAAGUCUAUUCUUUCAAGUGGAGCUAACCAGGAUAAUCUUUGUCCCCAAAGGCAAACCUUUAAAAUAAAUAGAUCAUUAAAUCUUCACUUGUGGAAAUGAGUUUUAGGGAAGGGAUUGAGUCUUGGAACAUGACUUUCAUCCAGAUAUCUAACGACAUAAUAGAAUGCAUAAUUAGCUCUGUGCCUCAUGCAUUAUUGCCUUCUAAAAUUACAUAAAUGAUUAAUGGGCAGACAUAAAAGUGGGCUUUAAAGAAAUCUAGUAAUAAUAAAAGCUGAAAAAGAAUAAUUCACUGCUGAUAAUUCAGAACCUGCAAAGCAGCACAAUAGAGUAAUGUGGGCUGUAGGCGAGCCCUCCCCACUCUUCCCCCACACCUGUGCCACACCCCCCUUACCCCAAGCCAGUUGUGCCCCCAGUUUCAAUCUCCUGCAUAACCAGGAGGUGCACUCCUAACCCUAAGCAACUGUCCUAUAAGUCAGUCAGUGUUUAUUGAUCACACAGGAAGUAAAGAGCCUUAGUGAGAAGUCCAUCACCAGGUUUAUCUUUAUACCAGACUUUAACUGAUCAUGACCCUAUCUUGCUACCCCUGGAUAUUUUCCACAUUACUUGGGACAAAUGGAAAGCAACCUCUGCUCUCCAUGAUCUGUUUUCACAUUGGUUAUAGCAUCUCUUGGAUGGAGUAGAGGGAGGUCAGGAGAAGAAGCCCACAUAGAUAUAUAACUGUCUUCUCUCAGAUUACACAUUAUAGCAUUAAAGGUUUUGAUUAAAAUCUAAUUGUAAGAUACUGCUGAUUACAAUUACCAAAAUAGCAUCACAGGAGAUUCAAUUAAAAUUGUUAUGGAAAUAAUUUUUGAAAUAGUUUAAAAUGCAAGAAUAUUCAGCGAUGUUAAUAAUUUAGAGAUACUAAUAAGUGUUCUGCUAGAUAGACUAUUUGAAAACUAUAAAUGUAUUUUUGGAUUAACAAUGCCAAGGUAUUUUUUCAUAUUCACAUUGAAAAAUACAGGCAAAACUAUCAAUAUUUUUUCUGCAUUAUAUGAAAUUUCACAGGUAGAACUAAAUCUAUGAUAUAGAAAAUAAUAGCACAUUACACAUAGAGAAAACCAAGCCACUUAGGUUUAGAUAGAUAUAUAACAUGUAACAUCUUCUCUGUUAACCAAUUAUAGAUACAUAUACAACAUGUAAUGUUUUCUUAGUUAAACAAUUGGAAAUGUUUAGGCAUUUUACUGUGUGGGGGCAGUGAGUAUGCACAUGAUCAGACUUGUAUUCUAGCUUUACAAUUAAAAUUCACAGAAUCAUUUCCUAAAGAUUUUAUUAUCCUUUCAUAAGUAUAAAUAUAUAUACUUUUACAUAUAAAUAGUUCUGCAUUUAGAAGGUAUCCUACACAUCAAACAUCCAUUAAACAUGUACUAUGCCAAAAGUUAGAGCUUAUACUGUUGUGGGUCUGGAGUUGUAGGAGGAUGGAUCAUGGUAUGGAAAUGCAGAAGUGCCUGAUGCAAAGAUCCUUGCCUGCAGGUUAAACAAAGCACCACAUAUGUAGACAUAGCACACAUAUGCAAAACAACUAAGAAAAAGACCUCCUUAGGUCUUUGCGUAACACACACAAAGAUAAAUGUAAAAAUUAUAUAGUUGAUUUAUAUGGUUUAUGUAACAAAGAGAAAAACUCCUUAAUGGACUUAUCCAAAGAUGAAAUGGACUGACUCAGGAAACAGUGGGCUCCCAGUAAUUCAAAGGUGACAUCUGCAUGGGCAGGAAAGAAGUUAAAAGCAAAUCCCAUGUGCCAAUAACAACCAGAUGGCUUGGAAGUAGCAGAGACUGCCGAAGAGCAGGAGAAAAUAAGAUUGCUAAAAGAGAAAGAGUCAGAGGAAGGGAGAAUAUUAACUCUUAGGAUAAAAAGUGACAUAACCGGCCAUAGAAAGUUACCAACUGUUCAUAAGUAAAGGAAGAAAAUAAUUAUUGUAGUGUUUGAGGAAAAUUAUGCUUUUGAUCCUUUGUGGAAUAGAACCAAAGAAAGCAAGGUUCCAAGGAUUAAGUUUCUUACUGAAGGAAUAAGUUUGGUUAAUGGCUACAAAAGUGAAAA